GAUUGGUGUUGGGUUUAUUUGUCGGAGAGGCUCCUGAGCGCUAGGUCGGCACUGCGGUGACUGAACCCAGAAGGCGGAGAACAGUUGUCCUCUGCUGCACAGAGGCGACUCUGGAGCUCUGUGACGGCGCCAAGCGUGACCCACCCCUGGGCCAGGAUAGGGACCGUCAUGCCCAUAUCUCCUGGCUGGUCACCCUCUCCUCCCAACCCUGCUUUAAACCACGUGGUUCGAUGGCGGUGGUGGCCACGCUGAGGCUCUCUGCUCAGGGCACAGUGACUUUUGAAGACGUGGCUGUGAAAUUUACCCAGGAGGAAUGGAAUCUCCUUAGUGAGGCUCAGAGAUGCCUGUACCGUGAUGUGACUCUGGAGAACCUGGCACUUAUGUCCUCCCUGGGUUGUUGGUGUGGAGUGGAAGAUGAGGCGGCACCUUCUAAGCAGAGUAUUUAUAUACAAAGAGAGACUCAGGUCAGGACUCCUGUGACAGGUGUGUCUCCCAAGAAGGCCCACCCCUGUGAGAUGUGUGGCCCGAUCUUGGGAGACAUUUUGCAUGUGGCAGAUCAUCAGGGAACACAUCACAAGCAGAAACUGCACAGGUGUGAGGCCUGGGGGAAUAAAUUGUAUGACAGUGGAAACUUUCAUCAGCACCAGAAUGAGCACAUUGGAGAGAAACCCUACAGAGGGAGUGUUGAGGAGGCGUUGUUUGUGAAGAGGUGUAAGUUGCAUGUGUCAGGGGAGUCAUCUGUCUUCAGUGAGAGUGGGAAGGACUUUUUGCCCAGGUCAGGAUUACUCCAGCAGGAGGCCAGUCACACUGGGGAGAAGUCAAACAGCAAAACUGAGUGUGUGUCUCCCUUUCAGUGUGGGGGAGCUCACUAUAGCCAUGGAGAUUCCAUGAAACAUUUUAGCACCAAACAUAUACUCAGUCAGCACCAGAGACUUCUCCCUCGAGAAGAAUGUUAUGUGUGCUGUGAAUGUGGGAAAUCCUUUAGCAAAUAUGUUAGCUUCAGUAAUCAUCAGAGAGUUCACAGUGGAAAAAGACCUUAUGAAUGUGGAGAAUGUGAGAAAUCUUUUAGUCAAAAGAGCAGCCUCAUUCAACAUCAGCAAUUUCACACUGGAGGAAAACCUUAUGGGUGUGAAGAAUGUGGGAAAUAUUUUAGCUUAGAAGGAUAUCUUAGGCGCCAUCAAAAAGUUCACGCUGGAAAAGGGCCUUAUGAGUGUGGAGAAUGUGGGAAAUCUUUUAGUUCAAACGUGAACCUUAAGAGUCAUCAGCGCAUUCACACUGGAGAGAGACCUUACAAGUGUGGAGAAUGUGAGAAAUCUUUUAGUCGGAAGCCCAGCCUUAGUUACCAUCAGCGCAUUCACACUGAAGUAAGACCUUACAAGUGUGGAGAAUGUGGGAAAUCUUAUAUUUCAAAGGGGCACCUUAGGAUCCAUCAGCGCAUGCACACUGGAGAAAGACCUUACAAGUGUGGAGACUGUGGGAAAUCUUUUAAUGAAAAAGGACACCUUAGGAGUCAUCAGCGAGUUCACACUACAGAAAGACCUUAUAAGUGUGGGGAAUGUGGGAAAUGUUUUAGUCACAAGGGUAACCUCAUUCUACACCAGCAUGGCCAUACUAGAAAAAGGCCUUAUAUGUGUUGGGAAUGUGGAAAAUUAUUUAAGAAGAAGUCUCACCUCCUUGUACACCAGAGAAUUCACAGUGGAGAGAAGCCAUAUGCUUGUGAGGCUUGUCAGAAAUUUUUUAGGCACAAGUGCCACCUCACUGCACACCAGAGAGUUCACACUGGAGAAAGGCCAUAUGAAUGCAGUGAUUGUGGGAAGUCAUUUACCCACAGCUGUGCAUUCAUUGUUCAUAAGAGAGUUCACACUGGUCAGAAGCCUUAUGAGUGCAGUGAAUGUGGGAAAUCUUUUGCUGCAAGCUCCUAUCUCACUAGUCACAGGAGAGUUCACACUGGUCAGAAGCCUUAUGAGUGCAGUGAAUGUGGGAAAUCUUUUGCUGGAAUCUCCAGUCUCACUAAUCACAGGAGAGUUCACACUGGAGAAAAGCCUUAUGGGUGUAGUGAAUGUGAAAAAAAAUUUAGGAAAAGCUCUUCACUUCGUUACCAUCAGAGAGUUCAUGAAAGAAAGGCCUUAUGAGUGCAGAGAAUGAGUCCAGUCUCAUUAAAUACAGGAGAGCACACACCUGAGUAAGAUCUUGUGAUUGCAGCAAAUGUGGAAAAUGUUUACCCAAAAGAAGUCUGCUCUCCUUGGACAUUGGAGAGUUCACACCAGAGAAAAGUCCUUACAAGUAAAAUAAAUUUGGCAGUUUUGUAGCCACACCUCUGUAUUCCUUCAGGAUUAUAUUUAACACUGAAUGAAGGCCUUACUAGUGUGGCAAAUAUAGGCUAUUUAUCCAGAAGUCUGGCUUCAAAACUCACAGGAGAGCUGUCACUACGGAAAUGCCUUUUGAAUGUAAUGUUUGCAAAAAAGCACUGUGCCUUCUGUCAUUGAAUCCUAGAACACUGAGAUGAGAAAAACACUGUAGAUGUAUAGGUUAGAUAUAUAGGGAAUGUUAUUAUUUUUUCCUUUUUUUGGAGAGACGGUCUCACUCCAUCACCCAUGCUGGUGUGCAGUGCUGCGAUCGUAGCUCACUGCAUCCUCCGCCCCCUAGGCUCAAGUGAUCUUCCCACCUUAGCCUCCAUGUAGCUGGGUCCACAGGCAUGCACCACCAUGCCUGGCUAUUUUCUCAUAUUAGUAGAUAUAGGGUUUUACCAUGUUUCCAGGCUGGUAUCGAACUCCUGAGCUCAAGCAAUCUGUACACCUCAGCCUCCCAAAGUGCUGAGAUUGUAGGUUUGAGUCACUGUGCUCAGCCAAUUAUGUUUUUCUGUGUAACAUGGGAGGAGAUCCUUUGAGGGCACCAUGUGCCCAAAUUGAAAAAACUCCAGGCAUGUGGCAUCUGUAUUAUAUUUUUUACUAUGCCCUGUUAUCUUGCUAGACUUAUGUGACUGCCACUUAUCUGGCAAAAGCCAUUACAUCUCAGCUACUUGGUAGGUACCCACAUUGCAUCAUUCACCUAUUUCGUAUUCUAGAAGUAUAUUUUGGUUGUCUCCCAUUCACGAGAGAUUUUUUUUUUAAGUUUUUUGUUUGGUUGGUUGGUUGGUUGGUUGGUUGUUUUUUUUUGUUUUUUUUUUUUUUUUUUUUGGAGACAAAGUUUCACUGUCACCGAUACUGGAGUGCAGUGGUGUGAUCCUGGUUCAUUGCAACCUCUGCCUCCUGAGUUCAAGCAAUUCUCCUUUCUCAGCCUCCUGAGUAGCUGGGAUUACAGGUGCCUGCCACCACACCCAGGUAAUUUUUGUACUUUUAGUAGAGAUGGGGUUUCACUAUGUUGGUCAAACUGAUCUUGAACUCCUAACCUCGUGAUCCACCUGCCUUGGCCUCCCAAAGUGCUGGGAUUACAGUGUGAGCCUCUGCUUCUGGCCUUUUUAAAAAUUUUUUAAAUUUAUAUUUUUUGUAGAGACAGGGUCUUGCUGUGUUGCACAGUCUGGUCUCAAACUGCUGGUCUCGAGUGAUCCUUCUGCCUGGCUUCCCAGAAUGUUGGGAUUAUAGGCGUGGCAUAAGUCACCAUGCUGGGACUUUUUUAUUUCUUUAAUUUUUAAUUCCAGAUCUGGUCACAGAAGGAUUUGUUGAGUAGCCUCAGCACUUCUUGCUUUUUCAUUUCUUUCUGAUAAGUUACACCAUGGACCUUCCCCAUUUUUGUCCCAGAGGACUCUUGUGCUGACUUGAAAAGAUGGACUAUUUUGGCUAAGCAUGGUGGCUCAUGCCUGUAAUCCCAACACUUUGGGAGGCCGAGGUGGGUGGAUCACAAGGACAGGAAGGAGUUCAAGACCAGCCUGGGCAAUAUAGUGAAAUCCUGUCUCUUCUAAAAAUAUAAAAAUUAGCCGGGCAUGGUGGCGCACCUGUAGCCGCAGCUACUCAGGAGGCUGAGGCAGGAAAAUUGCUUGAACCCCGGGAGGUAGAGGUUGCAGUGAGCUGAGAUCAUGCCACUGCACUCCAGCCUGGGUCCUGCUACCUUGAAGGACAGCAUAGCUAAACUGCGUGGCCCAAGGGACAGCAUGAAUGCAGAAUAUAGCUUUCUUCACUUGUGGCCUAUUUGCAUAGCUGCCCAAGGCCUCCAGUGGACGACUUCAUGGCUUUGUGGUCUUCAUCUGUAGCAUGGAUACUACAGAUUGUGGGUUCAUAGGUCAGCUGGGUACAGGGCAGUUUUUAUAACAACCUCUGGUGGGUUUUUUAUUUUAGUGUCAAUAUCACACUGAAAGAUUGGUGAUUUUUUUUGAACCAGACAAAAUUCUCUCUUAUGAGGUAUAUUGCACUGUGCUCGGUACUGUUGAGGGAACUCUGUUCAGCAGAUCUUACAAGGCACACAUGUGCCAUGAUAUCCAGAAUUCUGUAAGGCAACAUCACAGGUUGUAAGGCUAUAGGAUGAAAUUAUAAUUUUAUGGUUACUUAGUUACUGCAUUUAUAGUCAGCAGAGGGGACAGCAAUAAAGUUUUUGAAAUAUAUCUUUUUUUUUUUUUUGAGACACAGUCUCACUCUGUCACCCAGGCUAGAGUGCUGUUGCACCAUCUCGGCUCACUGCAACCUGUGCCUUCUGGGUUCAAGCGAUUCUCCCACCUCAGUCACCCAAGUAGCUAGAAUUACAGGUGCAUGCCACCACACCACUAAUGUUUUGUGGUUUUAGUAGAGACGGGUUUCACCGUGUUGCACAGACUGGUCUUGAAUUCAACUCUUGAGCUCAGGUGAUCUGCUCACCUCCGCCUUCCAAAGUGCUGGGACUACAGGUGUGGGCCGCUGUGUUUGGCUGAAAUGUAUGUCUUUUAAAGGAGUGUCCACAGUUAUCCAGUCACUGUGUCUGUGAUGGAUAAGCAGAUACAGAAAUUCUCAAGACUUCCAUAAUAAUGAAUGUUGUGUAGCUAAGCUUUGGUCAGAGGAAAUAAUCUAAAGGUUUUGUGAAUUCAUGUAACCUUUUGGGCUGCUCACCUUAAGGUAACUCCUGUAUUAACAGGAGGAACAGAAUAGGGAAAAAGAUCUCAGUUCAGUGAUGUAGCUUUGUGACCAGCCAGUGAUCCAGUUCAAUCAGGUAGAAAUGACCUUCCUGCUACAUCAAUAUUUGCUUCUAUGGAGGCUAGUUUCCCCACUUAGGGCAUGAGAAGAAUUGGUAAAGUCAACAUAAAAUUGCCAAACCUGUCACCAAAAAUGAUGGCAAAUCUGUAUUUUUCUCUUAAACCGUGUUAUAAAAGCUGUAAUAAGGUAUAGGCUGAGCAUCAUGGCUCAUGCCUGUAUUCCCAGCACUUUGGGAGGCCAGAUUCCUUGAGACCAGUGUGGGGAACAUGGCAAAACCUUGUCUCUAGGAAAAAUAGCCAGGUAUGGUGGCAUGUACCUUAGUCUUAGUGAUGUGGGAGGAUUGCUUGAGCCUGGGAGGCAGAAGUUGCAGUGAGCUAAGAUUGCAACGCUGCAGUCCAGCCUGGGUGAUAGAGUGAGACCCCAUCUUAAAAAUAAAAUAAAGAUAUAAAUGACAUCCAAUAAAGUACACAUAUUUGAGCUGUAGGAUAAGUCUUGAAUUUUAUUAUAAUCCCGUGAAACCAUCAUCAGAGUCACCAUAAUGAAUUUAUCUAAUCUAUCACCUUUGUAUUUACUUGGAGCCUUUAUAAAGUUUUUCUCUCUGCUCUUCAAACAACCAUUGAUUUACUUUGCUGUAUGAUGGAGUACUUUCCAUUUUCUGGAAUUUUCUGACUGAUGUAAUAAAGUGUUUCCUCUUAUAA